AGGCGCCGCGUGGGGCCGGCACCUCCCGGCAGCAGCGGCAGCUGAGACUCACGGUCAAGCUACGGCGAGGAGUGGGUGGCUGAAGCCAUACUAUUUUAUAGAAUUAAUGGAAAGCAGAAAAGACAUCACAAACCAAGAAGAAAUUUGGAAAAUGAAGCCUAGGAGAAAUUUAGAAGACAACGAUUAUUUGCAUGAGGACACGGGAGAGACCAGCAUGCUAAAAAGACCUGUGCUUUUGCAUUUGCAGCAAACAGCCCAUGCUGAUGAAUUUGACUGCCCUUCAGAACUUCAGCACGCACAGGAACUCUUUCCACAGUGGCACUUGCCAAUUAAAAUAGCUGCUGUUAUGGCAUCUCUGACUUUUCUUUACACUCUUCUGAGGGAAGUAAUUCACCCUUUAGCAACUUCCCAUCAACAAUAUUUUUAUAAAAUUCCAAUCCUGGUCAUCAACAAAGUCUUGCCAAUGGUUUCCAUCACUCUCUUGGCAUUGGUUUACCUACCAGGUGUGAUAGCAGCAAUUGUCCAAGUUCAUAAUGGAACCAAGUAUAAGAAGUUUCCACAUUGGUUGGAUAAGUGGAUGUUAACAAGAAAGCAGUUUGGGCUUCUCAGUUUGUUUUUUGCUGUACUGCAUGCAAUUUAUACUCUGUCUUACGCAAUGAGGCGAUCCUACAGAUACAAGUUGCUAAACUGGGCAUAUCAACAGGUCCAACAAAAUAAAGAAGAUGCCUGGAUUGAGCAUGAUGUUUGGAGAAUGGAGAUUUAUGUGUCUCUGGGAAUUGUGGGACUGGCAAUACUGGCUCUGUUGGCUGUGACAUCUAUUCCAUCUGUGAGUGACUCUUUGACAUGGAGAGAAUUUCACUAUAUUCAGAACAUAGCUGACAAAUUAACUUCAGUAAAACUCAACUUGGAUCAUAUGUUUUCUUUUCUCAAAAUCUUCCCUAAAUGGGUCCUCACACUUAAAAGGUAAGUCCUUAGUCCUUACCUGGCAUUCACACUUUUCUAUAAUCUCAACCCAGAUUCUUCUGGUCUAAUCAACAAUUUUAUACCUCCCCAAAAAAGUCAAUUUACUCACUUUCUUCCUAAAAUGACUUUGACUCCAUGGCCUUGUUCACAUUGUUCACAUUCUUUAUUCACCAAGAAUACCUUUUUUCUCUCUUCUUUCCUCUUCAAAGUCUACCCAUUCUUCAAAUGCAAGACAGAGUUUACUUCCAUAUAGAUUUCUAUAGUCAUCCCAGCCUGAAGGAACUCCUUUCUCUCCCUUUCGCUCUCAUGAUAUUUUUGUUGUAUCAUUCUUAAAUAAUGAUGAACUGCUUUAUUCUAUUAUGAAUUCAUAUUUCAAUAAGUAACACAUAUUAUCUAGCCAUCCAUACUGCAAACUUCUUAAAGGCAAGGACAAUGGCUUAUAUUUCUUUUCAUCCUGUGAGAGACAUAGCUUGCAUUUAAUAAACAUUUAUUAUAUAUCUGGAUAAUUAUAGAUAUGAAUAUAGAUAUUAGUGUCACUAUACUAUGGCACUCAGUUUUAAAAAGAAACCUUCAACACACUAGCUUCAACCAAAGUCCACACCAGACAAGAGCUGUUCAGUAAUUAGAAAGAUACUCCAAUUCUAAAACGAUGUGCACUUACUACUACAUAUCUGCAGAAAAUGAGUUGCUACUUUUCAAAAUGAACGGAAUUGCUGAAGCAAUAAUCUAGAUUAUUUUAACCAACAGUUAUAUACUCCUACUUCAAGAUAGCUAUCUACAAUGGUUAGAUAUAUCACGUACUGCUAUUUUGCUCUUAAAGGAGUUUGUUUGAACUGAAGCAUAGUCAGCACAAAUUACUUCUAGGAAACCAUUUCUGAGAGAAUUUGGCUCUUUACAUCUUUGGCCAGAAUUCCUUGACUUUUGGCUUCCAGUCUGUAUUUUGCUUUCCUGGUAGAAAUGUGUACUCCUAGUAUCUUGCUGGCAAGGAUGCCUCUGCCAAAAGGAAAUACACACUACUUUCUUCAUGAAAGAACGGGAACACUCUCAGGUAGACUAUUGGCAUGUAGUCUAAGUGAAAUGAGCCCACCCAUCAUUACAACCUUACCAAAUAUGUAAGACGCUUCCAAGUAUUGUGGAUAAACACUCCUAGGUGUUGUGCAUAUACAAAAUCAUCCAGAAGUUACCCUAGAAAGGACGGUAAUACAAAAUAGUAUGCAUGUUCCAAGAGAAUAAUAAUGUGUCAUAAAUAAUUACAGAAGGUAGAGUUUUUUUGAGUUUGGAAAGCUCAGGAAAGGUUUCAAAAGGAAACGGAUCUAACCAAUGGAUCAUUUAGUAAACAUGGACCAUUUAGUAGAGUCCCACAAGAGACAGGACUAAAAAUGACAUAUUCUAGGCCAAUAGGAUAGAAAAAGAGGGCUUACAUAGAGGCAUAAUAAGUAAAAUAAGGUAGGCAAUUUGGAAAUACACUAGAGAAAAGCUUUAAAAUUCUGUAUUUUAUACUAUAGACAAUGGAGAUUUUUGAGUUUUCAAGCACCAGGAAAAUAGUGUUUUAAUACCAAAUUGAGAUAUAAUUGUCAGUUUUUUAAAAAAAAGUUUUCUAAAAAUAAAAUAAAAUCACUAAAAUAAUUUUGAAGAAAAAGAUAAAUCGAAAAAGAUCUUUUGGAUUGUUUUCAAAAAGAUAGAAAACAUUCUUUUGGAAUAGAAAUUACGCAUAGCUUGGAAUGGAAUUAAUAAAGCUCAAAGUCAGAUCAUGAAUAGGAAGUAUAGAAUUCAAGCACUUCAGAGGCUGGACCAUGAAAGGUAACAUUAUAACUAAAAUAAUUCAGCACUUUUAUUCACAUUUAGUGCUUUUUUCCUGAUUAUAAAAUAACCCAGAUAUACGGAUAGGAG